AGUCGGCGCGCGGGCCGGGCCGGGCCGGCGCCCCUCUGCCUCGCGCGCUUGUCGCGUUGCCCCGGGCUCCGGGGGAUGCCCCCGGCCGAGCCCUUCUCAUGGCCGCCGACGUCUUCAUGUGCUCCCCGCGCCGGCCUCGCAGCCGGGGCCGCCAGGUGCUGCUCAAGCCCCAGGUGUCCGAGGACGACGACGACUCGGACACGGAUGAGCCGUCCCCGCCGCCCGCCUCCGGCGCGGCCACCCCGGCCCGGGCCCACGCGAGCGCCGCGCCACCGCCGCCUCGGGCCGGGCCGGGCCGCGAGGAACCUCCGCGCCGCCAGCAGAUCAUCCACAGCGGCCACUUCAUGGUGUCGUCGCCGCACCGAGAGCACCCGCCCAAGAAGGGCUACGAUUUCGACACGGUCAACAAACAGACGUGCCAGACCUACAGCUUCGGCAAGACUAGCUCCUGCCACCUGUCCAUCGACGCCUCGCUCACCAAGCUCUUCGAGUGCAUGACUUUGGCCUACAGUGGGAAGUUGGUGUCUCCAAAGUGGAAGAAUUUCAAGGGCCUGAAGCUACAGUGGAGAGACAAGAUCCGGCUCAAUAAUGCCAUCUGGCGGGCCUGGUACAUGCAGUAUCUGGAGAAGCGCAAGAAUCCUGUGUGCCACUUUGUGACACCCCUGGACGGCUCUGUGGACGUAGACGAGCACCGCCGGCCGGAGGCCAUCACCACGGAAGGGAAGUACUGGAAGAGCCGCAUCGAGAUUGUGAUCCGGGAGUAUCACAAGUGGAGAACCUACUUCAAGAAAAGGCUACAGCAGCACAAGGAUGAGGACCUCUCCAGCCUGGUCCAGGACGAUGACAUGCUGUAUUGGCACAAGCACGGGGAUGGAUGGAAGACCCCCGUCCCCAUGGAGGAGGAUCCCCUGCUGGACACAGACAUGCUCAUGUCGGAAUUCAGCGACACCCUCUUCUCCACACUUUCUUCACACCAGCCGGUGGCCUGGCCCAAUCCCCGGGAAAUAGCACAUCUGGGAAAUGCAGACAUGAUCCAGCCGGGACUGAUUCCUUUGCAGCCUAACCUGGACUUCAUGGACACCUUUGAGCCUUUCCAGGACCUCUUCUCUUCUAGCCGCUCCAUUUUUGGCUCCAUGCUACCUGCAUCUGCCUCAGCACCUGUACCAGAUCCCAACAACCCACCUGCACAGGAGAGCAUCCUGCCGACCACAGCCCUCCCCACUGUGAGCCUUCCUGACAGCCUCAUCGCGCCCCCUACCGCCCCAUCCCUGGCUCACAUGGAUGAGCAGGGCUGUGAACACACCUCCCGGACUGAGGACCCGUUUAUCCAGCCCACGGACUUCGGUCCCUCAGAGCCGCCACUGAGUGUCCCGCAGCCCUUCCUCCCUGUCUUCACCAUGCCCCUGCUGUCUCCCAGCCCCGCCCCACCGCCCAUCUCCCCCGUGUUACCAUUAGUUCCUCCUCCUGCCACUGCCCUGAACCCCCCGGCUCCACCCACCUUCCAUCAGCCACAGAAGUUUGCUGGAGUCAACAAAGCGCCGUCUGUCAUCACCCACACGGCCUCUGCCACCCUCACCCACGAUGCCCCCGCCACCACCUUUAGCCAGAGUCAGGGCCUUGUGAUCACCACCCAUCACCCUGCCCCGUCAGCGGCCCCUUGUGGGCUGGCACUGUCUCCUGUCACCCGGCCUCCCCAGCCACGGUUAACUUUUGUGCACCCCAAACCUGUAUCCUUGACUGGGGGCAGGCCUAAGCAGCCCCACAAAAUAGUGCCUGCUCCCAAACCAGAGCCCGUGUCCUUGGUGUUGAAGAAUGCCCGUAUCGCCCCAGCUGCCUUUUCAGGCCAACCACAAGCGGUGAUCAUGACGUCAGGGCCUCUGAAGAGAGAAGGGAUGUUGGCCUCCACCGUGUCCCAGUCCAACGUGGUCAUUGCGCCUGCUGCCAUCGCCAGGGCUCCUGGGGUCCCGGAGUUCCACAGCAGCAUCCUGGUGACAGAUCUCGGCCAUGGCACGAGCAGCCCGCCUGCCCCCGUCUCCCGGCUCUUCCCAAGCACAGCGCAAGACCCCCUGGGGAAGGGCGAGCAGGUCCCGCUGCAUGGGGGCAGCCCCCAGGUCACUGUCACAGGGCCCAGUCGGGACUGCCCAAACUCAGGGCAGGCCUCUCCGUGUGCAUCGGAGCAGAGCCCCAGUCCUCAAUCUCCCCAGAACAACUGCUCAGGGAAAUCCGACCCCAAAAAUGUGGCUGCACUAAAGCAGAACCGGCAGAUGAAGCACAUCUCAGCUGAGCAGAAAAGGCGCUUCAACAUCAAGAUGUGCUUCGACAUGCUCAACAGCCUCAUCUCCAACAAUUCCAAGCUGACCAGUCACGCCAUCACACUGCAGAAGACUGUGGAGUACAUCACCAAGCUGCAGCAGGAGAGAGGCCAGAUGCAGGAGGAGGCCCGGCGGCUGCGGGAGGAGAUCGAGGAGCUCAAUGCCACCAUCAUCUCCUGCCAGCAGCUGCUCCCUGCCACGGGAGUCCCCGUUACCCGGCGCCAGUUUGAUCACAUGAAAGACAUGUUUGACGAAUACGUGAAAACCCGGACCUUGCAGAAUUGGAAGUUCUGGAUUUUCAGCAUCAUCAUCAAGCCGCUGUUUGAGUCGUUCAAGGGCAUGGUGUCCACCAGCAGCCUGGAGGAGCUGCACCGGACGGCGCUCUCCUGGCUGGACCAGCACUGCUCCCUGCCCAUCCUCAGGCCGAGUUAUAGAAGCUUAAUAUCAGAACAGCUGGCAGCCCCAUGGCACCAGGAACAGCAUAGGAUGCUCCACCUACGGCAGCUCCUGGAUUUGGGGAGGCUUCUGGAGGCAGAGGGUGGUAUUGAGCACGCUGCGGCAGCUGAGCACCUCCACCUCCAUCCUCACAGACCCGGCACAGCUGCCAGAGCAGGCGUCCAAGGCUGUCACCAGGAUUGGCAAGAGAUUGGGAGAGUCCUAGCUGCUUAGCUGGCAUGUGGCCGCAUGAGAUGCCAGGAGACCCUUCCCUGCCCAUGGAGAGUAGGCUGCGCCCCCCAGCCCUUCCUGACGCUCAGCCUCGGGGCCUCUCUCCAACUCUGCCGGCCCACCGUGGCAUCGGGAGGCCAUGCUCAGGUCUGAAGCAGGUUUGGGGCCUGCUGACAGCAAUAGCCCGCCUUUGGGAACCCCUUGCUGUGAACUCUCUCACUCAGUGACCUCAGUCACCAACCUCCUCUGCCCUCGGGGCAGCCCACACAAAAGGGAAGUGCUGGCCGUGCUGGUCCUGCCCUGCUGGUGGCCUGCCGGGCCUGGCGCCGGUGAGCGGAAUCGAUGGGAUGAGGGUGACAGGGCCUGCUCCUGUCCUGAGGCCCAGCCUUGUCCCUCCUGCCACGUCCUGUCCACAUGCAUGCCUCUGCCUGAUGCCCUGCUCCACUCUCUGGUCUGCCCGUGGGGCAGUUGGAAGGCGUCUUUCUUUCUCCCCUCAACUCUGACAGCACCCAGCCCUUGUGGAUGGACUUGGGCUUCUAUUCAGGCUUAUGCAUGGCAGGCUGCCAGGGGGAAGUGCCUUCUUCAGAGGUCCUCCAGGACACAUGUGUGCAGAAACGGUGGAUGUGGAACACACAGGACCAGAAUGGAAGCGUGUGAUGCACGGUGGCUGCUCUGGCUGAGAGGCCCUGCUGGGCAUGUUUCAUCUGUCCCCUUUUAGCUCCACCUGACAUUGCAGGAUCCAUGGGGACUCAGCCCAGGGCCUUCUCGGAUGUCACCUCACCGCUGUGGCCCUUCUGCCGUUCUUCUCCACUUGGCUCCAGCUGCAGCUGUUGACAGAUCAAGCAUGUCCUGUGGGAGCUUAGAACCCUGAAGUUCUAGUGUCUGAAAGAUCAGACUCCACGUCCUGCUGUCAGCCUUGUCAUCUUGUCUGAUGUCUUUCAGCUGGGAGCCCCAAACCAGGACAGUUCUCGGACCAAAGAUGCCCCCACACUCAAAAGUCUGUCCCGUCUUGUGUUUGGAGAAGGAAACAAUGUUGGCAGGCAGCACUCUGUGGUGGUCAGCCCUCAGAGCUGUUUCUAGGCAUCUCUCAGAUCAGACAGCAAAGAAUCUACCCAGAUCUGGGCUGGGUGGAGGUGUGGCUGGGCUGGGGGCCAUUCUGAGCCUGCAGUGAGAGUUUGGCCCAGCCUCAGUCCUUGCUCUUCUCUGGCUACCUCUGCAGGGAGCUGCAGGGGCAAGCACUCUCUCCAGCACUCAGGAAGCCCGGCCGAGGGUACCUCCUCGUGGAAAGAAUGCACUUUAAAGCUCUGCUGAGGAGUUCGGAGCCCAGGCUUUCAGGCGACCUCUGCCCUCCCUGCCUCUCCUCACCCUCCCUCUCUUCCUGCAGGGCCUGGGAAGGGCUUUGAGGGAGCCUGGGAGCCAUGUGAAGAGGGGCACGCCUGGGCUGUCCCACAGUUUAGAUCCAGUUGGAGGUUCUCCCUGGCUCCUGCAGGCCUGCGGGGAUCUCUCCCCACUUCAGGCCUCCGGCCAGCUGCCUGCCCUCUUGUCUGUGCUUCAGCCCUGCACAAAAGCAGCUUGGUGACACCACUCAGCCACCCAGAGUACGUGUUUACAGGCUUUCCAGAUCACCUUCCUGUGGGGUGAACGUAAUGAGGCGGGGCUGGUCCUUGGAAUUUCCCCUGGAAAAUGGUAACAGACUCCAUCCUUGACCCGGGGAUGAGCAUGAAGGCAUUGUCCCAAAGGCAGAGGCCACCGUGGUAGGAAUUCCACCAAGGCCAGAAGGGAAAAAGGAAGAACCCACCGUGUCUGGCUGUGCGGGCCCUGGGGAGGGUCGUGAGUGCAGCCCCUCUCUACUUCUGUGCCUUUGUAAAACGUGUAGAUAACCGCAGUGGUUGGCUGAGCCAAGAACUCUCCUAAAUCAGUGGCUUUCUCCCCACCCCUUGCUGGGGAGUCAUUUUUAAAAAAAUCUGUGGGAUAUAAAAUUGGCCUCCUGCUGCUUCAGCCUACCUCUCCCUCUGCUGACUUAAUGUCGUGAUUCUGUUUCUUCAGAUAUUUAAGGCUGUUAGGUUGUGUGAGCCUUGAAGUGUGUGUGUGUGUCCCAGCGACUGUCCACUGUCCAGGAGAUGCAUGUCUUUGUAUUGGAGAUAUUUCUGUAACUCAUUCUCUUGGUGCUCACGAUUGCCAUGGCCAUAGGGCCACAGUGCCGUAUCUGCUGCAGACAUGAUUGUUUCUUGUUCUAGAGGUUUUCUUGUUUUCGAAUCUUGCCUGAUGAAUCCAGCCAGACCAAGGGGCCUAGAUUUGACCUCUGUCCUGGGCUCCUGGGCCAGGUGCAGGAACAUCUGAGGCCACUCUGCUGGCCACCUCCAGUGGGUGCUGACCACAGGAUGGGCUUUGUUUACACUCAUUUUCACCCUGAUUCUUGCCCCCACUUUCAUAAAAGAAACUUCAAAAUGCUGACGCUUUGGAGAGUAAGAAAAUCAAUCUUGGCUGGGCACGGUGGCUCCUGCCUGUGAUCCUAGCACUUUGGGAGGCUGAAGCUGAAGGAUCACUUGAGCUCAGGAGUUGGAGACCAACCCUGGCAACAUAACAAGACCCUGUCUCUACAAAAAAAAAAAAAAAAAAAAAAAAUUUAGCCGUGUGUAGCAGUGAGUGCCUGUGGUCCCAGCUACUUGGGCCUGAGGCUGGAGGAUUGCUUGAGCCUAGAAGUUGCAGUGAGCUAUGAUCAUGCCACACUGUACUCCAGCCUGGAUGACAGAGUGAAACCCUGCCUCUAAAUAAAAGAAAAUAGAGGCAGACUGUGGUGGCUCACGCCUGUAAUCCCAGCACUUUGGUAGGCCAAGGCGGGUGGAUCACCUGCAGUCAGGAGUUCACAACCAGCCUGACCAACAUGGUGAAACCCUGUCUAUACUAAAAAUACAAAACAUUAGCCACGUGUGGUGGUACACGCCUGUAAUCCCAGCUACUCGGGAGGCUGAGUCAGGAGAAUCACUUGAACCUGGGAGGCGGAGGUUGCAGUGAGCUGAGAUUGUACCACUGCACUCCAGCCUGGGUGACAGAGCAAAACCCUAUCUCAAAAAAAAAAAGAAGAAAAAAAUAGAAAAUCCAAAAAGAAAAACCAGAAGGCCUGCUGGCGUAUAAAUCCCUGGGCGGGUUUCUGAUAAAUUGCCCUGUGCUGUCAGCCCCUGCACUGCACUGCUGCCUUCCAUGGUGGGUGGGAGACCCCAGAGCGGGGCAGGCGCCACUGAGGGCUUUUCUUGGAGUCGGCCAGCAGGCCACGCAGCAUCCGGCACCCUGGGCGGGCUGGCUAGCUGCCUUCUUAGGACAUCUCUACUUUGAAGGAUUUUACCGCAGGAAGCAAUAGCAGCGCUGGCCAUUGGUGCUGAUGACAGCAUUGGGUCUGGUUGAGGGGAAGGGGCUGGAAAGCAGCAGACCCCCCCAGUGCUGCGCAUGGUCCCGGAGCUGUCAGCCAGGGGAGUGGGGUCAGCCGUCAGCCAGCCCUCCCAUUUCCCGCCCAUGGGCCCUGACCACACUCCCUUUUCUAGAAGUCAAUCCUAAGGUUUCUCUGCUCUGGCUAAGAGGAUGUAAAUUUGGAUUCUUAGAGGGCAUGGCACCCCCAGUCCCUGCCCAGAUAAAGUAGCACAGUGGCAGGCAGCACCUCUGUCUGUUGCUGACGUUGGGGGGCUUACACACCCACCUCAUCUCCGUGCACAGCCAUGACUGGCCCUGCCGGCAGCUGGGGUGCAGGUAAGGGUCUCUCUCAUAGAGGGGAGCUGCAGCUGAGAACUGGCGAGGCCCCUUCCUCCAAGGCCCUAGCUGGCCCCCGGGUGAACCUGAGGUGGCAGGUUCAGGUUUUCAAGAUGGUGAGGUCUCGCUGUCUGCUGGACAGUACGUUAGGCUCUCAGAACUCAUGGGUGUGGAGCUGGGCCUGUCCCGGGCCAGUGGACCCCUGUGUGUGGGGGAUUUGGGGUGCUGUGGGCCUGGUUAUGCACUGGCAGAUGGACCUUGCUUUGGUCCAGCUCUUUUCCUUACCCUGGCUCUGACGUGGGAAGGCUUGGAGGGCCCGUCUCAUCACCCCCGUUCGCCCUCAGCUGUCCCUUUCCCUUGUCGCCUGGCCGCUGCCUCGCCCGCCUGAGGCCUCCUAGCAGGCAGCCUGGGUGUGAGUUGAGCCUCUCUCUUUUCCCUCUGGUGGGAAAGUGGCCUUUCCCUCAACACCUGCUCCCCGGCCCCAGAGGAACCCACCUGUUUUGGAGCUCAGCUUGGCCCAGCGUUUCCUUGGGGAAGGGAAAGGAGGGCUGGACAGCACUGAUCCGGGCAGGCAGCGUGUGCAGCAGUGGCCAGCCAGAGUGCCAAAGAUGCACGGGGAUGUGGUGUGUGGCUCCGGGCCCUCGACAUCUCUGCUUUGGGGGAUUUUUACCUUGUCUGCACACUUGUCAGGGGAGAGGGGACAGCAAGGUGGGAGGUUGAAGAGCUUUGAGGCUCAGCAGCAUGUUUGUGGCAUUCGGUGGACACCAUGGCCUUGGGCGGCUGGACAGGUUUUUGUGAUGUGAGGGACACGCAUGGGGCACAUGGUAAGCUUGGCAAGGGCUCCAGGAACGCUGACGAAGGGUUUUAGGACCCCCACCCCCAUGCCUGUACCAGGGCUGGCCUCCAGAGCGGGUGAGGACAGAGCAGCUGUGGGCUUUUCAUUCUGAGGUCUUGGCCCCCCUGGCCACCGCAAGGGACUCUUUGCUUGUCAGGGCUUGCAAAAACCAACCUUCGAGAAAGAAAAGGGAACUCUUCACGUUGAAUGUUGACUUUGUGUGUAUGCGUGUGUGUGUGUGUGUGUGCACGCGCGCGUGUGCGUGUUGACUUCAUGGAAUUUUGUUUUGUGAAAUUCCCCUCCAAUCGUGUCAGAAUUUACCUCCAUGCCCCAGUCACACUGUUGGUUCUGCGCUCUGAACCUGGGUGUAGCUCAUUUGAAGGACUCUCUUCUGCGUUUCCUAACAGUUAUUUGGUGGUCUCAAGAGUUGAGGUUGUGGAGGGUUGGGAGAAACUGAAGUUCUAUACAUUUCCAUAGAGUUUACAUCCUGCAGUUAAAAGGCAGGGAGGGCUCAGCCCGGGCCCCACAGCUCCAGGCCAUCCCCUACGGGCUGCCCACAGUGCCCCCUUUUCUCUAGCCGAAUCUUUUUCGAACAGCCCGGGAAAGGAAAACGGAUUCACUUGCUGAUUUUGUUCACGGCGGAAGCACCAUGUUCCGUUCCUUUUUCAGGUUCAGUUUGUUGUGUAAAUGGCGGUUUUUUCUGGUGUGAGCUUUGGUGAUGGUGGCAGGGCUCCUUUGAAGAGAUGGUUCCACCUCGUGGUCUGAAGAACAAACCAGAGAAGAGUCUGGUUUGGCCAGAGGCCCCCUCCGGUCCACGUCACCCUGAGUACACCCCUCUGAUUGCUCUGCUGUCAAGAAGCACGUUUCCACCAGCUGUAUUCAACACUACAAUGCAUUUUUUAAACUAUAUUUGCAUCCAAGACAAUAAAGACACCUUAUUUUUUUUGAAAA